GUCUACAUUGAGACUACAGUUGAUAUGCCUACCUCCUGAGACACUAGUGUGUGAGUCUCCUCCUGGGCCCCUGGGCAAAUGGUUUUGGCAGCAUGACCAAGGCCUAAAUGGGGCUGAAGGCAAGCACAGGAGGAUGGGUCCCUUUUCAGGUCUGGAGAUGGAAUCACUGUUGCUAUAGCAGGCCUUUUUAUGAGACUAACCUGGCCUCUCCACUAAAGGAUGUGUGACUUUCUGGGGACAGAAGAGUACAGUCCCUGACAUCACACACUGCAGAGAUGGAUAACCAAGGAGUAAUCUACUCAGACCUGAAUCUGCCCCCAAACCCAAAGAGGCAGCAACGAAAACCUAAAGGCAAUAAAAACUCCAUUUUAGCAACUGAACAGGAAAUAACCUAUGCGGAAUUAAACCUUCAAAAAGCUUCUCAGGAUUUUCAAGGGAAUGACAAAACCUAUCACUGCAAAGAUUUACCAUCAGCUCCAGAGAAGCUCAUUGUUGGGAUCCUGGGAAUUAUCUGUCUUAUCUUAAUGGCCUCUGUGGUAACGAUAGUUGUUAUUCCCUCUACAUUAAUACAGAGGCACAACAAUUCUUCCCUGAAUACAAGAACUCAGAAAGCACGUCAUUGUGGCCAUUGUCCUGAGGAGUGGAUUACAUAUUCCAACAGUUGUUACUACAUUGGUAAGGAAAGAAGAACUUGGGAAGAGAGUUUGCUGGCCUGUACUUCGAAGAACUCCAGUCUGCUUUCUAUAGAUAAUGAAGAAGAAAUGAAAUUUCUGUCCAUCAUUUCACCAUCCUCAUGGAUUGGUGUGUUUCGUAACAGCAGUCAUCAUCCAUGGGUGACAAUGAAUGGUUUGGCUUUCAAACAUGAGAUAAAAGACUCAGAUAAUGCUGAACUUAACUGUGCAGUGCUACAAGUAAAUCGACUUAAAUCAGCCCAGUGUGGAUCUUCAAUAAUAUAUCAUUGUAAGCAUAAGCUUUAGAGGUAAAGCGUUUGCAUUUGCAGUGCAUCAGAUAAAUUGUAUAUUUCUUAAAAUAGAAAUAUAUUAUGAUUGCAUAAAUCUUAAAAUGAAUUAUGUUAUUUGCUCUAAUAAGAAAAUUCUAAAUCAAUUAUUGAAACAGGAUACACACAAUUACUAAAGUACAGACAUCCUAGCAUUUGUGUCGGGCUCAUUUUGCUCAACAUGGUAUUUGUGGUUUUCAGCCUUUCUAAAAGUUGCAUGUUAUGUGAGUCAGCUUAUAGGAAGUACCAAGAACAGUCAAACCCAUGGAGACAGAAAGUAGAAUAGUGGUUGCCAAUGUCUGAGGGAGGUUGAAAUAGGAGAUGACCUCUAACUGAUAGAACGUUACUUUGUGUCGUGAUGAAAACUUUCUAAAUUUCAGUAGUGGUGAUGGUUGUAACUCUGCGAAUAUACUAAACAUCAUUGAUUUUUAAUCAUUUUAAGUGCAUGAAAUGUAUGCUUUGUACACGACACUUCAAUAAAGCUAUCCAGAAAAAAAAAAAAA